GCACUUAACCUCUGCCCGUCCGGCGCGAAGUUAGAGGCCCGGGCGGCGCGGACGGCGCGCACUCCCGGCGGUAGGGAGCUGAGGCAAGGGGCCCGAGCCCAAGCCCGCGGCCGCGGCCCGGCCCACGAUGACUUGCUACCGAGGCUUCUUGCUGGGCAGCUGUUGUCGCGUGGCGGGCGGCCGGGCGGCGGCGCUGCGGGGACCGGGUGCGGGAGGCCCCGCCGCGCGGCCCCGGCUGGGCGGUGACGGUGGCGGCCGGCGGCACCUGGGGCAGGGGCAGCCGCGCGAGCUGGCGGGCUGUGGCAGCCGCGCGGACGGCGGCUUCCGCCCCUCCCGGGUGGUGGUGGUGGCCAAAACCACCCGGUACGAGUUCGAGCAGCAGCGGUACCGUUACGCGGAGCUCUCGGAGGAGGACCUGAAGCAGCUGCUUGCAUUGAAAGGCUCUAGUUACAGUGGACUUCUUGAACGACAUCAUAUUCACACCAAAAAUGUAGAACAUAUUAUAGAUAGUUUACGGAAUGAGGGAAUUGAGGUUCGUCUAGUAAAGAGGAGAGAAUAUGAUGAAGAGACUGUUCGAUGGGCAGAUGCUGUCAUAGCUGCAGGAGGUGAUGGCACAAUGCUGCUGGCAGCGAGUAAAGUCUUGGACAGACUUAAACCAGUUAUAGGGGUAAACACUGAUCCAGAACGGUCUGAGGGUCAUUUAUGCCUGCCCGUUCGAUAUACACAUUCCUUUCCAGAAGCCUUACAGAAGUUCUAUCGUGGUGAGUUCAGGUGGUUGUGGAGGCAGAGAAUCAGGUUAUACCUUGAAGGGACUGGCAUAAACCCUGUACCUGUGGACCUUCACGAGCAGCAGCUAAGCUUGAAUCAGCACAAUAGAGCCCUUAACAUUGAAAGAGCUCAUGAUGAAAGGUCUGAGGCUUCAGGACCCCAACUUCUGCCAGUGAGAGCACUAAAUGAAGUCUUCAUUGGGGAGAGUCUGUCAUCCAGAAUGUCUUAUUCUUGGGCUGUAGCAGUGGACAAUUUAAGAAGAAGUAUACCCACUCUAAAGGGACUGGCUUCCUACUAUGAGAUUUCAGUUGAUGAUGGUCCAUGGGAAAAACAGAAGAGUUCAGGGCUCAAUUUGUGUACUGGAACAGGAUCAAAGGCCUGGUCAUUCAAUAUUAACAGGGUUGCAACUCAGGCUGUAGAAGAUGUUUUAAAUAUUGCAAAACGACAAGGAAAUUUGAGUCUUCCAUUGAACAGAGAAUUGGUAGAGAAAGUAACAAAUGAAUAUAAUGAAUCACUGCUCUACAGUCCGGAAGAACCAAAAAUACUUUUCAGUAUUCGAGAACCAAUAGCAAAUAGAGUUUUCUCAAGCAGUCGUCAGCGUUGUUUCUCCUCAAAGGUUUGUGUUCGUUCUCGUUGUUGGGAUGCCUGUAUGGUUGUGGAUGGAGGAACUUCUUUUGAGUUUAAUGAUGGUGCAAUUGCUUCGAUGAUGAUCAAUAAAGAAGAUGAGCUUCGAACUGUGCUUCUUGAACAGUGAAGGAUUUCCUCAUGACAAAUUUUGAUUACUGGCGAGAAUAUUUUUACUUCAGAAACAGACUACCAGUCGUAAAGUGACAUUUUUUGGUUAUUGUUGAGACUGCUUGCCCGUGGGCUCAGAAGUGAGAUUUGCAUUAUUCUUCUGUUGGAUUCUGAUAGAAAAAAAGACAUUCACUGUAUAAGAAAAUGGAUGGACUGAACCAAUUAGAAUUGAUACCAGUGAAAUUUUUAUAUUGCUUACAAUUGGUAACCAAGAGUGCUGAUACCUUUUUAAAUUUAGAGGGGCAGGCUUAAAUAAAGGACUAAAUAUUUAGGAUUUGAAACUUAACUGUAUAAGUGUGUUUUCCUUCCCUUUCCUCCUAAUUGUGGGAUUGUCAGAACUGAACACAUAUCAUUUGAUUAGUGCAUAUUUUUUAUAGUACCUGAAAACCAAGAUUUUGAAAAAAUUUUCAAGACAGAGAAUUUUGAUAAAUCCUGACAUUGACCUAAUUGACAUAGGUAAAUAUGUUUGUAUAUGUGCUAAUAAUUUUCUAAUUUCGGAACACGAUGAUGUUAUGACUAUUGAUUUAAAAAUUUCAAAUAAUAAUUUUUGAAAUUAUAGAUGAAUGCUUUCAUUUGAGUUUCAUUCUGUAAUUCAGCAGUUCUGGGUGAAAUACAGAUAGCAAAACAAAUCAUGAUGCUGUUACAAAUGUAUUAGUUAUCCAAUAAGUGUUUUAAGUCAAUUUUUUUAAAAUGAUAUGAGUCUUACAGGUUUCUUCCAUCUUUAAAAUGCUCAAACAUGGAUUCAGGGACUAAAAGGAUGAACUGAUUAGACAUUUUCUAUUAGGAGUUUGGUAAAAUAUUGUAAAAAUAUCUUCACCUGUGUUAGGAGUAUUAUCAGAAAGAAUGGAUUCUUUAAUAAAUAUGUAAAACACAGUAGUUUUGGAAUUGCCUUCCUUAGUAUUGUGGUUUUCACCUAGCUUAUAUUCCAAGAUUUACAGAAUAGCUUUUAGGAUAAGAUGUUAGGACUUUUUUUUUUUCCCCAUGAGAAUUCCUUUAUUUUUGGAGGAAAUUAUUAUCUAAUUAUUGAUCUACUUAUAAGUAAUCCUAGAAUUUUUGCCAAAAGAUCCUGUCGUUGCAUAAUCAAACAGUUGGUAUUCUCGUGCCGUUGUUCAAAGUCAUGUGUUUCUUUCAUUUGGUGCUGAAAAUUUCUGUUCAAUCAUUGACAAAUAUUUAUUGAACACCCACUCUGUGCCAUGUAAAACUAUGUCAGGUGCUGGAUAUGUUGAUGAAUGAAACAGACUCUAUCCUUAUACAAUUUGAGUCUUGUGGGCUCAGAAGUAAAUUCUGUGAAAGCUGGACGGAUAGUCGAAUUGAGUGCUCUUAGUUUUGCCAAUAUUUAACAUGUUGUUCUUAUCAAUUUUUUAAAAUAAAUGUUAAUGUACAAAGUUAAUCUAGGUUUUGAUGUAUAUCCAGAGAAUCAAUUUUUCUUAAAGUAUCUGCGUAGACAUUCAUAGCAAAGAAUUUAUGACAUAUCAGAUAGAAAUACAUUAAAAUGUAGUGUUUUCCCAGAGAUUGAUCUGGCUUUUUUUUUUUGAUAUACAUAAGAUACCACUUUAUAAAGAAGCUCCAUACUAUAGAACCUCCCCUAACAGGCUUAAAAUACCUUCUUUUUUUUUUUUUUUUUUUUUGAGAACGGAGUCUUGCUUUGUCACCCAGGCUGGACUGCAGUGGCAUGAUCUCGGCUCUGCAACCUCCAUCUCCCAGGUUCAAGCGAUUCUCCUGCCUCAGCCUCCCAAGUAGCUGGGAUUACAGGCAGGCACCACUAUGCCUGGCUAAUUUUUUGUAUUUUUAGUAGAUAUGGGGAUUCACCAUGUUGGUCAGGCUGGUCUCGAACUCCUGACCUUGUGAUCUGCCUGCCUCGGCCUCCCAGUAUUGGGAUUACAGGCAUGAGCCACCAUGCCCGGCCUUAAAAUGCCUUCUUAAAGGAAAAAUGCCAACUCCAUCCUUAAUCUCAAGGAAAUCUGAUUGUCCAAAUAGAUCUGUUAAUAUGUAACAUAUUAAUAGGUAACUUGCUGUGUAAAAUUAUAAGCCAUAUUUUAAAAGGUUUUAAAAAUACUUAUUGUGCUCCAUUUGUGAUAUAAUUUCUAACAUUUCUGCUCUGUGAUGGGGGUUUAUUUGUAAGAAUAAGAGGCAAAGGAAUGUUAGCAUAGCAAAAAUGUGUUUGAAUGAGUUAACCUUUUAAUCGCAACCCUAUGUGAAUAAAAUUACUCCACUGUUACCUCUUCUUUUUAACAUUUCUUAUUUCCCUCUCAAGGGGUCAUUAUUUGAAAACUAGUUUUCACAAAAUGUUAUGUUUCAGAAGUGUUUCCCCACUGCUGUGUAUUAUUAUUCUGUGCCCUGUUGACUUCAUUCACUGUUAACAUUUGACAUAGAAUGAUUAGUUAUUAAAUCAGGGUGAAGUGCUUACCUGGUCAGUGUAGGCUCUUCAGAUAAUUUUGACUUAAUAUUUUUGAUACUCCUUGUGCAUUUACAUUCAUGGCCCCUGUACAUUAAAUCAUAUUACAUGUUUUACUA